ACUGGGAAGCUUCAAUAUAGCUGUGGAAGUCUGGACUCUACAAGAUCCUGCUGUAGACAUUCAACAACCAACCAGAAUCAUGGAAAAGCCCACUUCAAGCACCAAUGGGGAGAAGAGGAAGAGCCCCUGUGACUCCAACAGCAAAAAUGAUGAGAUGCAGGAGACACCAAACAGGGACUUAGUCCUCGAACCGAGUUUGAAAAAGAUGAAAACAUCAGAAUAUUCAACAGUAUUAGUGUUGUGCUACAGGAAGACUAAGAAAAUACAUUCAAAUCAACUCGAGAAUGACCAGUCCUGAGAGAACUCCAUCAAUCCAGUCCAAGAGGAGGAGGACGAAGGAUCCUCACAGGAGGACGAAGACCUAGACUCAUCUGCAGAAUCUUCAAAGCAGGAUGAAGACCUACAAUUACCUGAAGGAUCUUCACAGGAGGAUGAAGACCUAGGGUUAUCUGAAGGAUCUUCACAAGAGGAUGAAGACCUAGACUCAUCUGAAGGAUCUUUGAUGGAGGAAGAAGACCCAGACUCAUCUGAAGGAUCGUCAGAGGAGGGUGAGGAAGACUAAUUAAACAUGGAGAAACCAAAUUGGACAAAUCCUCACCACCAACGGUGAUGAUUACAAUAAAAUCAAGUUUGAGAAGCUGA